ACACUUUUGUGUGUGCUCUCAUUGCAAAUGGCUCGUACGAAGCAAACAGCUCGCAAGUCUACCGGCGGCAAAGCUCCGCGCAAGCAGCUUGCUACUAAAGCAGCCCGUAAGAGCGCUCCGGCCACCGGUGGCGUGAAGAAACCUCAUCGCUACCGCCCGGGCACCGUGGCCUUGCGCGAAAUCCGUCGCUACCAGAAGUCCACCGAGCUGCUGAUCCGGAAGCUGCCGUUCCAGCGCCUGGUGCGAGAAAUCGCCCAGGACUUCAAAACCGACCUGCGUUUCCAGAGCUCUGCGGUGAUGGCGCUGCAGGAGGCUUGUGAGGCCUACCUGGUGGGACUCUUCGAAGACACCAAUCUGUGCGCUAUUCACGCUAAACGCGUCACCAUCAUGCCCAAAGAUAUCCAGCUGGCACGUCGCAUCCGUGGGGAAAGGGCAUAAGUCUGCCCGUUUCUUCCUCAUUGAAAAGGCUCUUUUCAGAGCCACUCA